GUCGCCGCCGCGGAGCGGAGUCGAGCCGAGCUGAUUUGAUCGAGGAGCGCGGUUACCGGACGGGCUGGGUCUAUGGUCGCUCCGCGGGCCGCUCCGCCGGCUGGUGCUUUUUUAUCAGGGCAAGCUGUGUUCCAUGGCAGGGAACUUUUGGCAGAGCUCCCACUAGUAAGCGAUCUUCCGUCUUCUCACCUGGGGCCGGUUUUUGGGGGAGCUGUGAGGACGGGGCCUGUGACUCCCCUGGGCCUGGAUCCCAGCUCAGUUCCGAGUGCCGGGGUCCUCACGGGAGACCGCAGCGGUCAGAAUCAAGAUGCGCUUUUCUGAGGCGACUCCCCUCCCCGCCCCCAGCCCCAGUUUCGGGGAGGGAAGGAUCUGUGAGGGGGAGGGGUGGGAGAGAGUUUCGUCUCCCGGGAAGGAACGUUUCGGAGUUUAAUUUCGGAUUCUUGGUUUAGCUAGGCCGCGGGGGGUCGGAUAGAGUGGGCACAGGUACGGGAAGUGUGACUCAGCUCAAGACUGUGAGGCUACCUGUUCAGGACAGUUGUGGCGUGCUUUUACCUGGGGUUUCUUCGGGUGAUCGGCGUCGUGGUCUUUUGUCAUUCACUGUAUAUCUUGAGUGGAUUUAAUAUUAUGAGGAGAGGAGAGAGUCUGGCUUGUUUCUGCCUACUAACCGCUUCUUGCGCGUACUUUAUGUCUAGAUGGAGUUUUAUAUUGAUAAGGUAUAGGGCAGGUGCCCUCUAAAUUUAUCCAUUUCAUUAGCCUGUGCUUUAUAUUUUGUUUUAAAGGCCUAUUUUUCCAGUGACUUUGUUUACCUGUUUCUUUAACCUUUUUCAUGAAUAAGUUCUUGUUUCUGUCAGUGACCAUGUGAGAGCUAGAAUAAUAUUAAAAACAUUUAUCCCUAAAUACAUUUGUUUAAGCAGGCAGGAAGGUGCGUUAUGGGGUAAAUUGAACAUUUGAGUAGGCUUUCCACUGUAUAGUUGAAAGAUGAACAGAAUUUGACAAGGUAUCUUGGUAUAAUUUUUUAUGCUAAGAAAGCAUUAGUAAGUAAUUUAAAUUUCGAUUCUGUGAAUAGGAUCUGUUCCUGAUGUUCAUUUUUUAGCCCUUUGCAAAGAGAAAAAAAGAAACAAUGAACUCAGUAACCUAUUUAAGGAAAAGCAGGUUUUCCUCUUGCUAUAAAGUGAUUCUGUGGAGAUGACAUGUUAAAGAAGCUUUACCACUGAUCAUAUGUGUGUGUGUGUAUAUAUAUGUGUGUGUGUGUAUGUAUAUAUAUAUGUGUGUGUAUAUAUGUUGCAUUGUUUUCACACACUGAAAUAUUGCUUGGGCAAAAUUAAAGUAUCGAAAGUUUAGGUAUUGGAGUUAGAGCUCCUGAAAAAAAAAGUUUAGGUAGUGGAGAAGAGAUAUUCUGAUAAACUCUGAAAGAAGCUGAGAGAAUUGACAAGUAGCUGACUGUUGAUUUUUCAGUUUUUCAACUUAAAAAAAAAAGAUCCUGCCUUAUUUUCAAUAGUGUUCUCAUUAUGCUUUCAUUUAUUCAUAGCAUUCUAAAAAUAUGUUUUCACUUUUCAAAUAUAAAAUUAUUAUAAAGUUAAGUGUACUUCUUUGAAACUAUUCUUUUCUCCCAAUUCAAAUAGUCCUAAAAGAAGGGACCACUUUGCCUUGCUCAAAUCCCUUGAGCAGUCAUGGAGUUUCUUAUCUGGAAAAGGUAACGAGUGUGGAAGACAAGACAAUUCUGGAAAAACAAACGAAAAGAUUAUGAAAGGCCAUUGUCUUAGUUUGCAAUGGAUUUUGGAUAAACAAGAUCUGUUGAAGGAGCGCCAAAAGGAUUUAAAGUUUCUCUCAGAGGAAGAAUAUUGGAAGUUACAAAUAUUUUUUACAAAUGUUAUCCAAGCAUUAGGUGAACAUCUUAAAUUAAGACAACAAGUUAUUGCCACUGCUACGGUAUAUUUCAAGAGAUUCUAUGCCAGGUAUUCUCUGAAAAGUAUAGAUCCUGUAUUAAUGGCUCCUACAUGUGUGUUUUUGGCAUCCAAAGUAGAGGAAUUUGGAGUAGUUUCAAAUACAAGAUUGAUUGCUGCUGCUACUUCUGUAUUAAAAACUAGAUUUUCAUAUGCCUUUCCAAAGGAAUUUCCUUAUAGGAUGAAUCAUAUAUUAGAAUGUGAAUUCUAUCUGUUAGAACUAAUGGAUUGUUGCUUGAUAGUGUAUCAUCCUUAUAGACCUUUGCUCCAGUAUGUGCAGGACAUGGGCCAAGAAGACAUGUUGCUUCCCCUUGCAUGGAGGAUAGUGAAUGAUACCUACAGAACGGAUCUUUGCCUACUGUAUCCUCCUUUCAUGAUAGCUUUAGCUUGCCUACAUGUAGCCUGUGUUGUACAGCAGAAAGAUGCCAGGCAAUGGUUUGCUGAGCUUUCUGUGGAUAUGGAAAAGAUUUUGGAAAUAAUCAGGGUUAUUUUAAAACUAUAUGAGCAGUGGAAGAAUUUCGAUGAGAGAAAAGAGAUGGCAACCAUUCUUAGUAAGAUGCCAAAACCAAAACCACCUCCAAACAGAAAUUCCCUGAGUGAUUCUCCACUAGUGGCAGGGCCUGAAGCUGCAAGAUGAUGGUGGACAAGAUAAGGCAAUAAUCCUAUUGCCAAAGUUACUGGUAUUUUCAGUUUUAGUUAUUUUUAAGUAUUCAGCAUUUUUAUUUUAAGUAUUCAGCAUUUUCCAGGAAAUUACCAUAUUUCUUGCUGACUUAUAAAGGUUUGCUGUAUUUAUAUAUGAUUUUAUUAUGCCUUUGGACAACAGUUUUGGUUUUUUUUUUUUUUUGAAGAACACUUCUUGUUUUUCAUAAAUAGUAGGAAUAGGAUUUUAUAUGUAAGAUUUAAUUUUAUAGGAAAUUUGUUUAGAAGAAGCUGUAAUCUCUAUGUUGAGUGAUACCUGUAAUAACAAUGAAAUCCCAUACCCUAAUUUAAAGUUUUUGAGUAUAUAUGGACACUAACUUCCAGAAUGCUUGUUAUAUGUGAGGGCACAAAGUUAUAUAAGAAUAAAAACAUAAAACCAA